AUUCGAAUCGGCGGCGGCUUCUAGUUUGCGGUUCAGGUUUGGCCGCUGCCGGCCAGCGUCCUCUGGCCAUGGACACCCCGGAAAAUGUCCUUCAGAUGCUUGAAGCCCACAUGCAGAGCUACAAGGGCAAUGACCCUCUUGGUGAAUGGGAAAGAUACAUACAGUGGGUAGAAGAGAAUUUUCCUGAGAAUAAAGAAUACUUGAUAACUUUACUAGAACAUUUAAUGAAGGAAUUUUUAGAUAAGAAGAAAUACCACAAUGACCCAAGAUUCAUCAGUUAUUGUUUAAAAUUUGCUGAGUACAACAGUGACCUCCAUCAAUUUUUUGAGUUUCUGUACAACCAUGGGAUUGGAACCCUGUCAUCCCCUCUGUACAUUGCCUGGGCGGGGCAUCUGGAAGCCCAAGGAGAGCUGCAGCAUGCCAGUGCUGUCCUUCAGAGAGGAAUUCAAAACCAGGCUGAACCCAGAGAGUUCCUGCAACAACAAUACAGGUUAUUUCAGACACGCCUCACUGAAACCCAUUUGCCAGCUCAAGCUAGAACCUCAGAACCUCUGCAUAAUGUUCAGGUUUUAAAUCAAAUGAUAACAUCAAAAUCAAAUCCAGGAAAUAACAUGGCCUGCAUUUCUAAGAAUCAGGGUUCAGAGCUUUCUGGAGUGAUAUCUUCAGCUUGUGAUAAAGAGUCAAAUAUGGAACGAAGAGUGAUCACGAUUUCUAAAUCAGAAUAUUCUGUGCACUCAUCUUUGGCAUCCAAAGUUGAUGUUGAGCAGGUUGUUAUGUAUUGCAAGGAGAAGCUUAUUCGUGGGGAAUCAGAAUUUUCCUUUGAAGAAUUGAGAGCCCAGAAAUACAAUCAACGGAGAAAGCAUGAGCAAUGGGUAAAUGAAGACAGACAUUAUAUGAAAAGGAAAGAAGCAAAUGCUUUUGAAGAACAGCUAUUAAAACAGAAAAUGGAUGAACUUCAUAAGAAGUUGCAUCAGGUGGUGGAGACAUCCCAUGAGGAUCUGCCCGCUUCCCAGGAAAGGUCCGAGGUUAAUCCAGCACGUAUGGGGCCAAGUGUAGGCUCCCAGCAGGAACUGAGAGCGCCAUGUCUUCCAGUAACCUAUCAGCAGACACCAGUGAACAUGGAAAAGAACCCAAGAGAGGCACCUCCUGUUGUUCCUCCUUUGGCAAAUGCUAUUUCUGCAGCUUUGGUGUCCCCAGCCACCAGCCAGAGCAUUGCUCCUCCUGUUCCUUUGAAAGCCCAGACAGUAACAGACUCCAUGUUUGCAGUGGCCAGCAAAGAUGCUGGAUGUGUGAAUAAGAGUACUCAUGAAUUCAAGCCACAGAGUGGAGCAGAGAUCAAAGAAGGGUGUGAAACACAUAAGGUUGCCAACACAAGUUCUUUUCACACAACUCCAAACACAUCACUGGGAAUGGUUCAGGCAACGCCAUCCAAAGUGCAGCCAUCACCCACCGUGCACACAAAAGAAGCAUUAGGUUUCAUCAUGAAUAUGUUUCAGGCUCCUACACUUCCUGAUAUUUCUGAUGACAAAGAUGAAUGGCAAUCUCUAGAUCAAAAUGAAGAUGCAUUUGAAGCCCAGUUUCAAAAAAAUGUAAGGUCAUCUGGGGCUUGGGGAGUCAAUAAGAUCAUCUCUUCUUUGUCAUCUGCUUUUCAUGUGUUUGAAGAUGGAAACAAAGAAAAUUAUGGAUUACCACAGCCUAAAAAUAAACCCACAGGAGCCAGGACCUUUGGAGAACGCUCUGUCAGCAGACUUCCUUCAAAACCAAAGGAGGAAGUGCCUCAUGCUGAAGAGUUUUUGGAUGACUCAACUGUAUGGGGUAUUCGCUGCAACAAAACCCUGGCACCCAGUCCUAAGAGCCCAGGAGACUUCACAUCUGCUGCACAACUUGCGUCUACACCAUUCCACAAGCUUCCAGUGGAGUCAGUGCACAUUUUAGAAGAUAAAGAAAAUGUGGUAGCAAAACAGUGUACCCAGGCGACUUUGGAUUCUUGUGAGGAAAACAUGGUGGUGCCUUCAAGGGAUGGAAAAUUCAGUCCAAUUCAAGAGAAAAGCCCAAAACAGGCCUUGUCGUCUCACAUGUAUUCAGCAUCCUUACUUCGUCUGAGCCAGCCUGCUGCAGGUGGGGUACUUACCUGUGAGGCAGAGUUGGGCGUUGAGGCUUGCAGACUCACAGACACUGACGCUGCCAUUGCAGAAGAUCCACCAGAUGCUAUUGCUGGGCUCCAAGCAGAAUGGAUGCAGAUGAGUUCACUUGGGACUGUUGAUGCUCCAAACUUCAUUGUUGGGAACCCAUGGGAUGAUAAGCUGAUUUUCAAACUUUUAUCUGGGCUUUCUAAACCAGUGAGUUCCUAUCCAAAUACUUUUGAAUGGCAAUGUAAACUUCCAGCCAUCAAGCCCAAGACUGAAUUUCAAUUGGGUUCUAAGCUGGUCUAUGUCCAUCACCUUCUUGGAGAAGGAGCCUUUGCCCAGGUGUACGAAGCUACCCAGGGAGAUCUGAAUGAUGCUAAAAAUAAACAGAAAUUUGUUUUAAAGGUCCAAAAGCCUGCCAACCCCUGGGAAUUCUACAUUGGGACCCAGUUGAUGGAAAGACUAAAGCCAUCUAUGCAGCACAUGUUUAUGAAGUUCUAUUCUGCCCACUUAUUCCAGAAUGGCAGUGUAUUAGUAGGAGAGCUCUACAGCUAUGGAACAUUAUUAAAUGCCAUUAACCUCUAUAAAAAUACCCCUGAAAAAGUGAUGCCUCAAGGUCUUGUCAUCUCUUUUGCUAUGAGAAUGCUUUACAUGAUUGAGCAAGUGCAUGACUGUGAAAUCAUUCAUGGAGACAUUAAACCAGACAAUUUCAUACUUGGAAACGGAUUUUUGGAACAGGAUGAUGAAGAUGAUUUAUCUGCUGGCUUGGCACUGAUUGACCUGGGUCAGAGUAUAGAUAUGAAACUUUUUCCAAAAGGAACUAUAUUCACAGCAAAGUGUGAAACAUCUGGUUUUCAGUGUGUUGAGAUGCUCAGCAACAAACCAUGGAACUACCAGAUCGAUUACUUUGGGGUUGCUGCAACAGUAUAUUGCAUGCUCUUUGGCACUUACAUGAAAGUGAAAAAUGAAGGAGGAGAGUGUAAGCCUGAAGGUCUUUUUAGAAGGCUUCCUCAUUUGGAUAUGUGGAAUGAAUUUUUUCAUGUUAUGUUGAAUAUUCCAGAUUGUCAUCAUCUUCCAUCUUUGGAUUUGUUAAGGCAAAAGCUGAAGAAAGUAUUUCAACAACACUAUACUAACAAGAUUAGGGCCCUACGUAAUAGGCUAAUUGUACUGCUCUUAGAAUGUAAGCGUUCACGAAAAUAAAAUUUGGAUAUAGACAGUCCUUAAAAAUCACACUGUAAAUAUGAAUCUGCUCACUUUAAACCUGUUUUUUUUUCAUUUAUUGUUUAUGUAAAUGUUUGUUAAAAAUAAAUCCCAUGGAAUAUUUCCAUGUAACUUAGUUGUUAUAAAUAUUUCAACAAAAUAUACAACCCCAUAAGGUCCCUAUAUAGCAGGCUGAUUGGGCUGCUUCUGGGAUGCAAGCAUUUGUGAGAAUAAUUCAGACAUGAGCAUUCUCUAGAAAUCACUUUUUAAACACUGACCUGUUUAAGCCAAAAAAGGGCCAAGACAGCUAUUUUCCAAAUUUGAAGUUUGGUGUCUGUGUAAACACACACACACACACACACACACACACACACACACUUCCCUAACAUUUCCAAGGGACUUCAAGUUUUUAUGAAUAAAGCUUGCCUGUCCUUUA